AAAAAUAUGUAAUAUGUUUAUGUGAUUCAAAAUUCAAAAAGCACCAAAGUGUACAGUAGAAACAUAUUUUUCCUCCUUGUCUCCUGCCAUAGUUCAUCUACCCAGAAGCAAACCUGCAAAAUCUAUCUUAUGCAUAUAAAAACAUUUAGGCGCAAAUAUAAUUCUUUUCCCUUUUUUUGCACAAGAAUUAGCAUACUAUUUAGGGUUGCCAAAUGAAAUACAGGACAUCAGUUAAAUGAGCAGUAUUUGGGACAUAUUUACACUAAAAAAUUAAUUGGUGUUUCAUCUGAAAUUCAAAUUAAACUGGGUGUCCUGAAUUUUAUUGGCUAAACCUGGCAUCAGUAAAUUAUUAUCCACCCUAUUCUGCAUCUUGUUUGUCUGCUUUUUUUUCUUUUUUUUCUGCAUUGGAAUCAUCUAAAACUCUGUUAAAACUCCCAGGCCCAAGCUACACACUCCAAACCAAUUUCAUCAGAAUCUCCAAGGAUCAUUCUUGGGCAACAGUAUUUUUUUCUGUGAUUGUGUUAAAUUGAGGAAUAAUUUAACAAAAAAAGCACCCAUUUUAAGUGUACCAUUCAAUGAGUUCAAUGACAAAUCUAUACACCUCUUUUUACUUAAUAAUUAUUUUGGUGAUCACCCAAAAAUCAGUUCUUAAAUUGUAAACCCUUUAGAGCAAGCUUUGUAUUUUAUGCUACUUUUCUUCACAGGACUUGAGCAUUCUGUGUUUCAGAUAAAUACAGGUUGACUAACAACAGAGUUCUUUAUUUCAGUCAUUAUUUAGGUUUAAUGCACAAAAUGAGAAAUGUUAUUAAUGAGUUUUUGCAGUUGCAACACUUGUUACAAAGAAAUGCAAAGGUUGCGAAGAAAUAGUUGCAGACACUACUUAGUACCAAGAGAUCAUUUCCACCUACUCAAGAUCUCCCCACUGGCUAAGUGGUACGCCAGGUGCUUCACAUACACUGGAUGACCCUACAAAUCCCUACUUAUAUAGGAGGGAUCUGAGGCCCAGGUUAAAGAAAUUGUUCAAGCCACAUAGCUAAUAUUGAGAGGAGCUAGGAUUCAAACCACAUGUUUAACCCCAAAUUCUUAGUAAGGAUACUUCUCAAUAUGGCAUAAUUUUGAGAUUCCACCUUUCUUCACACUAUUCAGAAACUCCUAUUUUUAAUUUGGAAAAUGGUUGAGAACAGCUGUUUCUGUUUCUCAGCAGAUGCUUAUCUCAGCCAAAAUGCCUUCUUGAGAGAACCAAUCAAGAGAAACCAAACAGGUCAAAUUUCUUUAGGCUCAAGUUUCUUUGAUCUGUAUUAAAGCCUUUACAAGGUAGUUCUGGAUUUUGUGUUUGUUGGUUCACAUGCCUUGGAUCACCUGAGCAUGAAGGCUUAUUGAAAGAAAUAGUUGAAAGGAUAUAAUUAUAAGUUGUGAUUUCAGGGGAAAGGAAGUAGUGUCUUUUGCUAAUGAACCUUAUUGUUCCCCUCAAGUUGUGUGUAUAUCAUAUCCAUGUCUUGAUGUGCCACUAAAAAUGAAAGAAUUGACUUAAAACACUAAGGGUGAAUAUCUUGUUUCUGCAUAUGCCAACUAUCUUGUUUCUCUUCCUUUAUGGAUGUGUGUUUUGAAAUGCAGGAUGUAGACACAGACCACAAAACCAUUCUAGUUUCUGCAGCGGAGAACGCAAUAUGAGUAUCUGUCUCAAGGUCAUUUCCUGAUAAUAUUAUCUUCCAGUAAUUUGAGGCAUAGGUUCAGGGAGGAGAGUAGGACGGAAUUCUAUUCCUGGCUUAGCUGUUUUCCUCUGUCUCCAUCUUUAAAGCAAUUUUGAAAGUCUCUUGCAUAUGGUUGAUGUUCAGUAAAGGUUGGAUGAACUGUCUUGACGUUCUUUUUGAAAACUGAGGAUAUGCUGUGUUCCGAGUAACUUGGCAAUGUGUCAGUGAGGGCACAAUUAUGAGUCAGAGACCAUAGAACUGCAAUGGGAUCUUAAAUUCUUUUAAUUUUGGCAAUCUCAAUUCAUCUAGAAGCACCUUUAGAAGAGCAAUUGAUCUUGAAAUCUUAACAUUCAUCAAUAAGUAGAUGAGAAAGAAGUUUAUAAAGUCAUUGAAUUUCAGAGAGAACUUGAUGCCUGGCAGUCUAUGGCAAGUUGUGGACUUGCUUUAUGUAUAUAUAUAUAUAUCCAUGAAACCACAAUUUGAUUGAUUCCAGUAGUUUUGACUUGGGUCUUGGCCCAGAAUUCAAAAGAUAAUGCUGUGACAGCAACAAGGAAAUUGUUCUGAGAACUCAACAUAGCUGAAAUUUGUCCGCAAGCAGACCUACUUUCAGAGUCCAGUCCCUUACAGAACGAUUAAUUCAUCAGCUGCUGAAGAAUCAAGUCCAAAUAAAAUUAAUGGUACCACACAAGCUUCAUCCUUUAGUUUACAUAUAAUCUGGAGUCCUGGCAGAAAGGAUCUAGGAAAGCAUUUAAAGAAAAAAAAAAAAGCAUGACUGCCUUAGAAAAAUUGAGUCAUGCACCAACUUAAGAAGACAAGCAGAAAAAUUUUUGAAAUCAAAUGAUAAAUCUUUCCAAAAAUUCUUGAAGUGAGUUUAUUUAAUCCAAACAUUUAUAUAACAUCUCAGCGCAUCUGUUUUGAACCGACCAAGACCAUCACUAUGACCGAUGGAGACUAUGAUUAUCUGAUCAAACUCCUGGCCCUCGGGGAUUCAGGGGUGGGGAAGACAACAUUUCUUUAUAGAUACACAGAUAAUAAAUUCAAUCCCAAAUUCAUCACUACAGUAGGAAUAGACUUUCGGGAAAAACGUGUGGUUUAUAAUGCACAAGGACCGAAUGGAUCUUCAGGGAAAGCAUUUAAAGUGCAUCUUCAGCUUUGGGACACUGCGGGACAAGAGCGGUUCCGGAGUCUCACCACUGCAUUUUUCAGAGACGCCAUGGGCUUCUUAUUAAUGUUUGACCUCACCAGUCAACAGAGCUUCUUAAAUGUCAGAAACUGGAUGAGCCAACUGCAAGCAAAUGCUUAUUGUGAAAAUCCAGAUAUAGUAUUAAUUGGCAACAAGGCAGACCUACCAGAUCAGAGGGAAGUCAAUGAACGGCAAGCUCGGGAACUGGCUGACAAAUAUGGCAUACCAUAUUUUGAAACAAGUGCAGCAACUGGACAGAAUGUGGAGAAAGCUGUAGAAACCCUUUUGGACUUAAUCAUGAAGCGAAUGGAACAGUGUGUGGAGAAGACACAAAUCCCUGAUACUGUCAAUGGUGGAAAUUCUGGAAACUUGGAUGGGGAAAAGCCACCAGAGAAGAAAUGUAUCUGCUAGACUCUACAUAGAAACUGAACAUCAAGAACCCCACCAAAAUAUUACUUUUAAAAACAAUGACAAACCACACAAUUGUUGUUGAGUAAACCACGCACAAUGGCAUGUCUUUCUUUUUCUGCCAGAAAAUCUAUUUUAAGAAACCAGAAUAGUCAACAGUGUUCAAAAGAAUUGACUAGUUAUCCCUGAGGCCCUUUCAAACAUGAUCAAAGAUUUCCCAAUGUGAUCUCAUCAUCAUGGAUACUCAAUUUGUUUUUUCUUAUAGAGAAAAUGAGUAUAUAAGACAAUAUACAAGAAGAAAUAUCAGUGAGUUUUAAAUCAGAACAAGUUACCUGUCACAUUGAAGAAAAGGGUAGGCACUAAAGGGAGAACACAGAAAGAAGAAUUUCUAAAAUAUUGGAUUUACUUCUUAUAUUGAGUCAGAUGCAUACUUUUAGAUUUGCAUUGGGGAAAAUGUACUAGCUAAAAAUGGAUACACAAUGAAGAAUUCUAUUUGGCUAAUUAAGAAUGAUAUACUAUGUACACCCAAUAAGCUGUACUAGAAUGAAUAAAUUACUGAUAAGGUUACAAAUAGGUAAAUGUCACACUUCUGUUAAAAUGCAGGAGGUAGUGUCAUAAUGCCGUCUUUAUAUUCUUAAUAAAUAGCACUUUGACAAGAACAGGACUGUAAAUGAUGAAGUACAAGACAAAUACCCUGGGAAAAAAAAUGAAAGUAUGAGAAAUUGGCAUUUCUACAGCUGAAAUUCAAUGUAUCUGUUAGAGAUGUCUGGAAGGGUUACUUAGCCAAAUUUUACUCAAGCCAAUUAGGAGCUGAUAUUAUCAGUUGGAAUUAAGAGAACUCCAGAGGUUUCCAUUUCAAACAAAAUUUUAGAAAUUGGUUUGGUGUUCAGCUUCACAUUUCAUUUUUUCUUAGCACAUGUUGAUAAAAUAGUCACAAGGAGAAAUUACCAGUUACGGUUUAUUAAAUCUCUUUUAAAAUGCAGUCAAGGAAAACUAGCCUUGAAUUUUUUUUAGAUAAAAUAAGAUGGUGAUAUGAAACAAAAAGUGGCAAUUAUUGCAGGUUUCCUUUUAGUUUACAAAAGUACUGGAAACUAAAUCAUAUUUCUUCCCUCCAAAUUUCACCCAUUCCUGACUUUGAAUCAAUUGCAGAAAUGCAGGUGUGUUACUUUGUUGAUCAAUAACUUUGGAACAAUUAUGGAUCAAUUCUAUGGUCACUCUGAAUUUUCAUGUCAUUAAUCACAUAAAAAUUGAUAAUACCUCAUUCUGUAUUACAAUAUGAUUUUAUUUUGCCAAAGGCAAGACACCUAUAGUUGAGCUGUAUUUUGGGGGAUUGGGUGAGGAAGGACUUCUGAUCUUAUCUCAACAAAAAACUGGCCAGUAUUUUUGUUAAUGUAAAGCUUCCUUUUCUUUCUAAAAAAUAGUAACAAAAUUAUUUUUCAUUGGCCUAUUCUGUUCUUGUGUCUAAACUAACAUUACAUUAAUUUUUAAUCUUAGUUUCUGAUAAACACAAGCCAUUCCUAUCAAAAUAUUAUUUAUUUCAGUCAAUUUUACCAAAUAACAAAGACAAUAUAUUUUCGUUUUUUUUUAUUAUGAGCAUAUGAUUUUUUGACAGGCUGUUUCCUCGUCGUAUAGAUUUUUUCCAAUCAAACCUACUUUUUCCAUACUCUGUGCAUAUUUUUUGUGAAGUUAUACACAUUGAAGACCCUAAAAAUCCCAGUCCAUCAUUCAGCUUACCUCUGCGAACUUCUAUCUGGUAUUGAAUCAGUUUCAGAAACACAGACAGAUCCAAGGAAAUGUCUCUUUAUAAUGUUCUUAGGAUGGACUAGACCCAUAAAUGUGCCAUGAAUCAAAAUAUUAAUAAUUUGAAAGCUUUCAUGCUGUUAGCCCCUGAUGAAAUUCUCAGCAUUAACUGGCCAGCUCCUCUGAUUUCUGCAGCAUCGCAACAGGUUCGAAGAUGGGUUGUGGCUGGGUAUUCCCUCCCAUGGUGUUUCCUCUGGGAUGCUCUUCAUUAUCUCAAUGCCUGUGCCAUGAAGAUAGAAAACUGUAAGCUAACAUUUAAGAUGUUUCUUCUGGAAGGAAAGUGAGCAGGAACAAGUUAUAUUGCCACUGCUGUGGCAAAUUUUGGUGAACUUUUGGGGUCAUUAUAUCAAUUUUUUCUUUGGAUUCAAAUUGUAAUGUCCCCUGCAUUUCCUUAAUAGGGAAUGUGAAACCUUUAUAAAACUCUAAAAGUAUUCUGUUUUGAUAUGUCUUUUUGUUUCUAUUCAUUUUCAGUUAUAUGAUUGAUUUACUUAUGCCAAGAUUCUGUCACUGUCAGUUAUUUAAUGAGUGUUUUUUCAGGGUCUGUUUUAAGAUCAUUAUUUGAUAGCUGUAGCAUGAAGCAGAGGUUGAUGAUGCCCAUAAUUGCAAGACUAUUCCUGUAAAAAUAACAAUUAUUGGGUAAUAACUUCAAGAGGAAUGAGAAGUGACAAAAUUGAUUUAAAAUAUUGUUCUACUUAUAAAUAAAUGCUUGAUAUAAAAAAUUUUCUCCAUAAAGUUUGACAUCUGACCCCAGAUUCUAUGUAAUCAUUAUUAGAAAUUCCUUCUCUCAUUAUUUCAGGAUUAGUAGUUCUGUGUAAUUCAUUUUACAAUUUCAAAUUGUUCUGGUGCCAUAAAGUAUACAGACUACUUUAAAGAUUUCCAAAUCCCCUAAUUUACCCCACAACAGCAUGUAAUUUUAGCCAAGAUAUGUCCUGUUACUAAGUAUCUCCCAAUGCUUUAGUAAAACGUAUUUAGGAGAAAUGUUGAAAAUGUACAUGAAGCUCCUUUCUGAUAUAGAAACCAUUUCUGGAGUAUUUACACUGGUUUGAUGUUUACAUUGCUCUAACUCGGUGCCUCAGAUACCUCUGUGACCAAAUUUGUCUCCAACCACAUAGCUCAUUUCCUAUAAUGUUAUAUCAUAGGAAGCCCUCACAGAGACACUAACACAGCUAAAGAUCUUCUGAUAUUAUCAGCAAGGGAUGCAAGGACUUUAUUGGAAUCUGGAGAGUUUAACUGCCUUCUCUUGGUCUCCUCACUUACUUCUUAUGAAGUUGGCAUUACCUGAGACUCUUAGCUGUGAUUAGGUACAAGCUUACCUUUUAGGGUAGAAAAAGAAAGAUCAUUUGAAAAAUGUAUCUAAAAUAAUCCAGAGAACAUAAUGUUUGUCUUGGUCUGAUAAUGAUAAGAAGUCAAGGAUUGGCAGAGAAAAUACUAAACGCCAAGAGUUGAGCCUGUGGGUCUCUCCAUAAGAGUUUUAAAACUCUUGCCAGUUACCACUUUAUCCAAUUUGCUAUCAUUUUCGUAUUAUCAGCUAUCGCCCUGUAAAAUAUUCAAAACUAGCUAUUUCUAAAGUAAACAUUUUAUCUGUUACUUUUAACCAGAUAGGUGUCUUUGUCAUCCUUCUACUAUAAAUUGUUCUUUGCCAACCUGUACAGGUAGAUGAACCAGGCGAGAGUUUUAAUCAGCCUUUUCUUGUCCCCUUUGUAAGAAAGAGAUGCUUGCCAUAGAGAAGGACAUGAGUACAUUAAAAAUAAUUUAAUAGCCACAAUAUGAUGUUCUUUAAGCUGCAAAUUGAGUACACUGGGAAUCAACAAAUUUGAUGAAGCCUGUCUGUCUCUUCACCAGUGGAGUGAGUGCAGCAGUUAGAAAGAGAAGCAAUAUUGUGCAACUGGUGCAGUGGUGAGUUAAUCAUAGUGUAUAACCUUGUGUUCAUGAAACAGGUUGUUCAUUGUUCUGCAUCUCUCUUCAUUUAAAAAGGAUACACAAUUCUUUCCUCAUUGCAUAUUACACCAAACGUUUGAGGGAAAAAUCCUCAUUCGUAAAGGAUUUUGGAUGUAUAAUCUAAAACUCAACAAUAAAGAAAUAAUAUUCCAAGUCUCUGGUUUCCUAAGAUACAUAAUAACUGUUUAUAAAGAAGGUCUAAGAGCUGAUAUUUGCCAAAGUGAUAGAAGAGUUGUUUUUUCCUCUCUACUACCAAGCUUUAAGACAUUAAAAGAAGUCUAGUGUAUUUGAAUAUUUUAGAGAAAGCUUUAUCAUUUUUUAAGAUGCCAAGAUGCUGCCUACGUUUGCAAAAGUUGUCUAAGAAUUCACCAUGAGCUAUAUUUUCUUCUGGAUCUUUGACCAAGGUGAUGUCAGCUUAUUUCUGGGGAAGGUGUUGAGCUCUUAUACAUGAAAAUGGAUAUAGGCUAUUCUCUGGGAUGAGUGUCAUUUCAAUGCUUUAUAAAUCCAUGAAGCUGCUUGUCUCAUAAAGUAGAACUGAUACAAAUUUUGGUUGGAUAUAUAGAGAAUUUUAUAAAUGUAUUGCCUUAGAAUUUCUGGGUGGAGACCCAACUACAAUGACAUUGUCAUGCCAGAACUAUAAAGAUAAUUAGAGUUAAAAGUUGUUUAAAUUGUGCCCUUAAAUACAGCAGAACCUGGAGAAGGUCAUACUUCAAAGGUCGAUUUUGAGUCCGAAUAAAGAAAGACCUAGUAACAGAUAGUUUUUUUUUGUUCAUUUUCUUCUACCAAGUAGAGGUUUAUGCCCUCAGAACUAAACUAGUAAAAAUAUCUGAACAAAAAACCUUUCGUUGUUGGCAUAAAAAUGUGAUACACUUAGAGACAUUUUGUUUAUUGCAUAUAAAUCUAAUUUUUCCAUAAAUUAGAUUUAUGAUAUUUUCAUAAAGCACUUGAUUAGUUUUUCAAGGCGUACCAUCACAAAGAUGCUUUCCUGCAGAGUUCUUUGUAUCAACAGCCUAUGGUUGAGAUGUUUUCUCAUUUCCUGUAGAGAGAGAAUACCACUAACAAACAAACAAAAACUUUAGUGCCAAAAUAGUGGAACUAUUUUGUCAUCUUUUGAGAAAAAAAUAUACAAAGAAGUCAUCUUUUCAUUAAGUGGAUUCCCUGGUUCCUUUCCAGCUGGUUGUGGAAGUAAUGGCUAACAUCCUUCAGCUGACUUUGUCUACAAGGAUUAUUAGCAAAUUCUGUAGGAGCAAGCAUGUCUGACCUUAACUUAAUGGAUCCCUUAUUCAAUCAGUGGCUUCUGUCUUUAUGUCUGUUGGCAUAUCAAAAUGGUUUCUGUUCCUAGAAAAGUAAUAACAUAUGCUUAUCUUUAUUCUUUUUCCAGGUGAUUUUGUUUUCAAAUGCUCCUUGUGAAAACACCUAGUGUUGUAGAAAGGAAAGUGGCCAGAAAGAACAACUUGGGACCAUGAGUAGGUCAUUAAAUAGCUUAGUGAUUUAUCCUCAUAUAGGGCUUAUAAACCCUGUAUGUGUUUAUAUGUGCUUCACAGAGUUCGUGUCAGGCUCAAAGGAGAUAUGUAUAAGAAAGUGGUUUGUAAAUUAUGUUCCAUUUCAUAAAUAGACACUAUUCACAAACUAAAAUCUAAUAAAAAACCACAGUUGUAAUUUAAACUGCUUGAUAUAAAAAGAGGUAUCAUAGCAGGGAAAACACACUAAUUUUCAUACAGUAGAGGUAUUGAAAACUGAAAAUGGGAAGGCAACUUGAAGUCAUUGUAUUUGAUUGAAAAUGUUUAAUACAUCUCAUUAUUGACAAAAUAUGUCAUCUUGUAUUUAUUUCAAGGAAACCAAUGAAUUCUAGGUAGUAUAUUACAAGUUGGUCAAAAUAUUCCAUGUACAAAUAGGGCUUCUGUGUCCAUAGCCUUGUAAGAGAUACUGAUUGUAUCUGAAAUUAUUUUUUAAAAAAAUAAAUUAUCCUGCUUUAGUUAGUGUGUUAAAAGUAGACGAUGUUCUAAUAUAACACUGAAGUGCUUCAUUGUAUCCCAACAGUUUACCUUCAAGUAAUAUUAUCUUUAUUUUUAGGCUAAGCACGUUUGAUUAUUUUGUCUGUCUCCUAUAUAGAUCUGUUUUGUCUAGUGCUAUGAAUGUAACUUAAAACUAUAAACUUGAAGUUUUUAUUCUAUAUGCCCCUUAAUAGACUGUGGUUCCUGACGCACACUGUUAGGUCAUUAUUUUGUUGUACCAAAGUUCUAGUGGCUUCAGAAAUCAUAGCAUCCAAUGAUUUUUUGGUGUCUGGCUAUGAAUACUAUGGUUGAGAAUUGUAUUCAGUGAUUGUUUCUGCACACUUUUCAAAUAAAAAAUGAAUUUUUAUCAAUUA